AGUUGCCAUGGUGAUUAGAGAAAGGCCGAGAUCUGUCCAGCUGCGAAUGGCGAUCAGUCCACGAAGCGAUGCAACUUUCUCCAGUCAGAAAUCAACACCUUCAGAGAGUCCUCGAACAAAGAAAUUUCCACUAACUGAAGAGGAAAUAUUUUAUAUGAAUUGUAGAGCUGCCUACUUAACUGUCUUCAAAAGCAGCUUGGAAAACAUUAUUUCUAAAGAUCAACUUUACUUAGCUCUUCAGCAUGCAGGAAGAAAUCCAUCCCAAAAGACCAUUAAUAAGUAUUGGACUCCUCAAACUGCCAAACUGAAUUUUGAUGAUUUUUGUAUAAUUUUAAGGAAGGAAAAACCUACUUCAAAAGCAGAACUACUAAAAUCAUUUAAGCAAUUAGAUGUAAAUGAUGAUGGCUGUAUUUUACACACUGACCUUUAUAAAUUUCUAACAAAGAGAGGUGAGAAGAUGACUCGAGAAGAAGUAAAUGCCAUAAUAAAUUUGGCUGAUGUAAAUGCUGAUGGCAAAUUUGACUACAUCAAGUUUUGUAAAUUAUAUAUGACAACCAACGAGCAAUGUCUCAAGACUACACUAGAAAAACUAGAGGUUGACAGUAAAUUGAUGCGUCACCAGUUUGGAAACCACAUCGAAGGGUCCCCUGAAAGGGACCCAUCACCAGUACCAAAACCAUCACCUAAAAUCACAAGAAAAACUGAUCCAGAAACAUUCUUAAAUAAAGGUGACACCAGGAGUUCUUUACUGUCAGCAACCAGGAAGUUCAAAACAUCUGUUUCCUUCACAGUUACCAUGGGGGCUAAUGGUAACCGAAACUCAAAGUUAAUGGAGCCAAAUUUAAUAAAGGACUGGCAACACAUGCAAUCAAAAGGUUGCUUCUUCUUAGAAGAAGAUGGUGAAAUCAUUAGUCAUCAGUACAGGAUGCAAAUAGCUCAGAGGUCCAUGGUUUAUCUAACAAUUAAGCCAUUAAACCUGAGUCAAGUUGAAGGAAAACCAUCCCCUUGGUUAUCCGUUGAUACUGCCUUGUAUAUUCUCAAGGAAAAUGAGAGUCAAGCAAAUCUACAGCUUGUGUGUUUUACCGAACUACGAAAUAGAGAAGUGUUUGGAUGGACUGGUGAACUAGGACCUGGAAUUUACUGGUUAAUUCCUUCCACAACUGGCUGUAGGCUGAGGAAAAAAAUAAAACCAGUAACAGAUGAAGCCCAACUUGUAUAUAGAGAUGAAACAGGGGAAUUAUUCCUUACAAAGGAAUUUAAGUCUACUUUAUCAGAUAUAUUUGAAGUAAUUGAUUUAGAUGGAAAUGGUCUUCUUAGCCUUGAAGAAUAUAAUUUUUUUGAAUUGAGAACAAGUGGUGAGAAAUGUGAUGAAGAUGCUUGGGCUGUCUGCAGAGAGAAUUUUGAUACAAAGAGGAAUGAACUAACAAGACAAGGAUUUAUGGAUUUGAAUCUAAUGGAAGCUAAUGAUCGAGAAGGAGAUCCUUGUGACCUUUGGGUAACUCUACACUCUAUGGGCUACAAUAAAGCUCUGGAGUUGACAGAGGCAUGUCCAUUUGUCAUUGAUAUCUAUGCAGAAAAAUGCAAGCCAAAAAUUAAAGCUGUCCAUAUGGAGGCAUGUAGUGGACAACUUGAGAAGGCCAUUUGUAAAUCUGUUCUUAGCAACGGUGAUGCCAAAGUAAUGGAUGGCUAUGAAAAUAUAAUCGUGCAUACUUACAGUUGUGACACCUGGAUAACGUCAGUUAUUGAAAACAAGUCAGAUGAGAAAGUGAUUAUUCACAUCAGCAAUGAGCUAAGUAAAAACUGCAUAAACAACAGAGGACUCAACAUAUUUGCAGUAGAAGUGGGACCCAAAUCUACAAUGCCUUGAAGGGAAAAGAUAAACACCAGCUGCCAGUCUUUUGGUUGUACAACAAGAAGGUCUGGACAAUGAGAACCCUUUUUCUAGAUUGGUUCCAUCAAUGCUUUGUCGCUGAAGUCAGGAAGUACUUUGCCAGUAAGCGACCACCUUUUACAGUUUUUUUGAUCUGGCACAAUGUCCCUGGCCACACGGAACCCCAUGAUUCAACACUGAAGGUGUCAAUGAGGUCUACUUGCUCCCCAAAACAAGGUUCCUAAUUCAACCUAUAGAUUGGAGGUCAUGAGGGCCUUUAAGUCUCAUUUCACGUGGGAGGUACUCUGUGGAAAGGAAUGUCAACGCUAUGGAUGAGAACCCCCAAUAGAGAGAAACCAUGAUAUGAAGCCGAGAUGGCCUUUUAGAAAAGAAAACUAUAUAAAAAUAAAAGACUGAAAGAUUAAAACAACAAUAACAAAAGGACAUCAUAAAAGUCUAUAAAGAUAAUACCAUUGAUUAUGCUACAGAAAAAGCCAUGAAAGUCAUCAAACCUGAAACAAUAAAUUCCUGAUGGAGAAAACUGUGUCCAGAUGUUGUGCAUCAUUUCACAGAAUUUAUGACAGACCUAAUCAAAGAAAUGAAAGACGUGGAUAUGGCCAAAAAAAAAAAAAAAAAAAAAGUGGGAGGUGAAAGGUUUUAAGAUAUGGAUCUUGGAGAAAUUCAAGACACCACACCAGAGGAGUUAAGACAACAGGAGAGAGUUGAGUGAUUCUGAACCAGUGCCAAAUGAUGUGGAAGAAGACAUAGAAGAAGCAGUGCCAGGAAACAAAAUGACAUGAGACAGUCUGGCAUAAGGGUUCUGAUUAUUCAAGAUCACUUUUGACUUCUUUUGCAACAUGGAAACUAAAGCAAACAGUGGAAGAUGGAUUGUACUGUAUAGAAACAUUUUUAGAGAAAUGAGAAAGCAAAAAAGUCAGACAAAAAUUACAGUGUAGCCGGGUGUGGUGGCUCAUGCCUAUAUCUCAGCACUUUGGGAGGCUGAGGUGGAAGGAUUGCUUGAGGACAGGAGUUCAAGAUCAGCCUGGGCAACAUGGUAAGACAUUGUCUCUACAAAAAAUAAAAUUAGCUGGGCAUGGUGGCACACACCUGUAGUCCCGGCUACUCAUGAGGCUGAGGCCAGAGGAUCACUUGAGCCCAGGAGUUCGAGGCUGCAGUGAGCUAUGAUUGCACCACCACAAUCCAGCCUGGGCAAUGGAGCAAGAUCUUGUCUUGAAAAAAGAAAAAAAUUACAGUGUAUUUCCAAGUUACACCAAGUGUGCCUGCCUCUUCUGCUUCUGCUACUCUUGAGACAGCAAGACCAACUUCUCUUCUUCCACCUUCUAUUCAACAUGGAGAUAAUGAGGAUGAAGACUUAUGAUGAUCCACUUUCACUUAAUGAACAGUAAAUAUAUGUUCUCUUAUGGUAACAAAUAACAUUUUCCUUUCUCUAGCUAACUUUAUUGUUUAUGUUCCAUAAGGCUUCUGGUCAACAUAGGCUAUUAGUAGUUAAGUUUGGGGGGAGUCAAAAGUUAUGGAUAGAUUUUCCACUUGUGGGGGUGGUUGGCAUUCAUAACCCCCAUAUUAUUUCAGGGUCAACUGUACAUUGUUGAGCAUUUUUGUGACUGCAUAAAAUGGAUGUUGGUCUGUAGUUUUCUUAAUUGGAAAUGUCUUUGUCUUGUUUGGGUAUCAGAGUAAUUCUGGCCUCAUAAGAUGAGUUGGGAAUGCUUUCUCGUUUUCUGGAAAAGACUGUAAAAUUGGUGUUAUUUCUUUAAAUGUUCACUUGAAUUUCUCAUUAGAAACAUCUAGGCAUGAAGAUUUAUUUUGGAAGAGGUUUUUUUUUUUUUAAUACAAAUUCAAUUUCUUUAACAGCUACAGGAUAUUCAGUUUACCUAUUCUUGGUUGAGUUUUGGUAGUUUGUAGUUUUUGAGCAUUUGGUCCAUUUUAUCUAAGUUGUCAAAUUUAUGUGCAUAGAAUUUUUUAAAAUUGUCAAUGCAGUCUGUAGUGAUAUCCCUUUUUCAUUUCUGAUAUUAAUAAAAUGUGUCUUCUCUGUU